GUCCUAUUCGGGCUCCCGCCUCUGUUCAGUUCCAGAGACAAUUCAUGGGUCUUGGGGCCACCGAGGCGCUGUCCCUGACCACCAGCACGAGACCCCUUUCUAUCGCGCCAGUCCUGUGGUCUCCGCACCUCUCCAGCUCCUGCACCCCCGGCCCCCGUGGUUCCCAGCCGCACAGUAGCGUGUCCUGGGUAGCGUGAGGACCCACGGGGCUGGGCAGGUGCCACGAGCCCGCCGCCUCUUCGCCGCCCGCCGCCUCUCCUCCUCUCCCGCCCGCCGCCUGGCCCUCCCCUACCAGGCUGAGCCUCUGGGUGCCAGAAGCGCGGGGCCUCCGGGAGAAUACGUGCGGUCGCCCGCUCCGCGUGCGCCUACGCCUUCUGCUCCAGUUGCUUUCCCAAUUGAGCGGAAAAGCCGGGGCAUGUUGCCGGGGCCCUGGGCGGGACGGUUGUGCCCUGCAGCCCGAAGCCCGCCGGGGCACCUUCCCGCCCACGAGCUGCCCAGUCCCUCUGCUUGCGGCCCCUGCCAACGUCCCACAGGACACUGGGUCCCCUUGGAGCCUCCCCAGGCUUAAUGAUUGUCCAGAAGGCGGCUAUAAAGGGAGCCUGGGAGGCUGGGUGGAGGAGGGAGCAGAAAAAACCCAACUCAGCAGAUCUGGGAACUGUGAGAGCGGCAAGCAGGAACUGUGGUCAGAGGCUGUGCGUCUUGGCUGGUAGGGCCUGCUCUUUUCUACCAUGGCAGCCCAGGGCUAUGGCUAUUAUCGCACUGUGAUCUUCUCAGCCAUGUUUGGGGGCUACAGCCUGUAUUACUUCAAUCGCAAGACCUUCUCCUUUGUCAUGCCAUCAUUGGUGGAAGAGAUCCCUUUGGACAAGGAUGAUUUGGGGUUCAUCACCAGCAGCCAGUCGGCAGCUUAUGCUAUCAGCAAGUUUGUCAGUGGGGUGCUGUCUGACCAGAUGAGUGCUCGCUGGCUCUUCUCUUCUGGGCUGCUCCUGGUUGGCCUGGUCAACAUAUUCUUUGCCUGGAGCUCCACAGUACCUGUCUUUGCUGCCCUCUGGUUCCUUAAUGGCCUGGCCCAGGGGCUGGGCUGGCCCCCAUGUGGGAAGGUCCUGCGGAAGUGGUUUGAGCCAUCUCAGUUUGGCACUUGGUGGGCCAUCCUGUCAACCAGCAUGAACCUGGCUGGAGGGCUGGGCCCUAUCCUGGCAACCAUCCUUGCCCAGAGCUACAGCUGGCGCAGCACGCUGGCCCUAUCUGGGGCACUGUGUGUGGUUGUCUCCUUCCUCUGUCUCCUGCUCAUCCACAAUGAACCUGCUGAUGUUGGACUCCGCAACCUGGACCCCAUGCCCUCUGAGGGCAAGAAGGGCUCCUUGAAGGAGGAGAGCACCCUGCAGGAGCUGCUGCUGUCCCCUUACCUGUGGGUGCUCUCCACUGGUUACCUUGUGGUGUUUGGAGUAAAGACCUGCUGUACUGACUGGGGCCAGUUCUUCCUUAUCCAGGAGAAAGGACAGUCAGCCCUUGUAGGUAGCUCCUACAUGAGUGCCCUGGAAGUUGGGGGCCUUGUAGGCAGCAUCGCAGCUGGCUACCUGUCAGACCGGGCCAUGGCAAAGGCGGGACUGUCCAACUACGGGAACCCUCGCCAUGGCCUGUUGCUGUUCAUGAUGGCUGGCAUGACAGUGUCCAUGUACCUCUUCCGGGUAACAGUGACCAGUGACUCCCCCAAGCUCUGGAUCCUGGUAUUGGGAGCUGUAUUUGGUUUCUCCUCGUAUGGCCCCAUUGCCCUGUUUGGAGUCAUAGCCAACGAGAGUGCCCCUCCCAACUUGUGUGGCACCUCCCACGCCAUUGUGGGACUCAUGGCCAAUGUGGGCGGCUUUCUGGCUGGGCUGCCCUUCAGCACCAUUGCCAAGCACUACAGUUGGAGCACAGCCUUCUGGGUGGCUGAAGUGAUUUGUGCGGCCAGCACGGCUGCCUUCUUCCUCCUACGAAACAUCCGCACCAAGAUGGGCCGAGUGUCCAAGAAGGCUGAGUGAAGAGAGUCCAGGUUCCGGAGCACCAUCCCACGGUGGCCUUCCCCCUGCACGCUCUGCGGGGAGAAAAGGAGGGGCCUGCCUGGCUAGCCCUGAACCUUUCACUUUCCAUUUCUGCGCCUUUUCUGUCACCCGGGUGGCGCUGGAAGUUAUCAGUGGCUAGUGAGGUCCCAGCUCCCUGAUCCUAUGCUCUAUUUAAAAGAUAACCUUUGGCCUUAGACUCCGUUAGCUCCUAUUUCCUGCCUUCAGACAAACAGGAAACUUCUGCAGUCAGGAAGGCUCCUGUACCCUUCUUCUUUUCCUAGGCCCUGUCCUGCCCGCAUCCUACCCCAUCCCCACCUGAAGUGAGGCUAUCCCUGCAGCUGCAGGGCACUAAUGACCCUUGACUUCUGCUGGGUCCUAAGUCCUCUCAGCAGUGGGUGACUGCUGUUGCCAAUACCUCAGACUCCAGGGAAAGAGAGGAGGCCAUCAUUCUCACUGUACCACUAGGCGCAGUUGGAUAUAGGUGGGAAGAAAAGGUGACUUGUUAUAGAAGAUUAAAACUAGAUUUGAUACUGAACACUGUCAGUGAUUCAUUUUUUCAAAGUGAGACAGCUUCCUUGGGAAAUAUUGUCAAUACCUGCUCUUUCCACCCCAAAAUGGAAAGACUUCAUUUCCCUGGAAUGGGGAAGCUGAAGUGUAGAUGGACUCCUUUAAAACUCAUGCCUCCUCUGCCUUCACCUGAACAUUGAAUAGUUCAAUGAUUAUUUUAGAGAUAAAGCUAUUGGGUUGUGGACAGAUUAAAUAACUUGAUGGAGGGAA